GGACGCAGGAGGCCUCGUGGAGGACACAGCAGCAUGGGACAGUCAGGGAGGUCCCGGCACCAGAAGCGCGCCCGCGCCCAGGCGCAGCUCCGCAACCUCGAGGCCUAUGCCGCGAACCCGCACUCGUUCGUGUUCACGCGAGGCUGCACGGGUCGCAACAUCCGGCAGCUCAGCCUGGACGUGCGGCGGGUCAUGGAGCCGCUCACUGCCAGCCGUCUGCAGGUUCGUAAGAAGAACUCGCUGAAGGACUGCGUGGCAGUGGCUGGGCCCCUCGGGGUCACACACUUUCUGAUCCUGAGCAAAACAGAGACCAAUGUCUACUUUAAGCUGAUGCGCCUCCCAGGAGGCCCCACCUUGACCUUCCAGGUCAAGAAGUACUCGCUGGUGCGUGAUGUGGUCUCCUCACUGCGCCGGCACCGCAUGCACGAGCAGCAGUUUGCCCACCCACCCCUCCUGGUACUCAACAGCUUUGGCCCCCAUGGUAUGCAUGUGAAGCUCAUGGCCACCAUGUUCCAGAACCUGUUCCCCUCCAUCAACGUGCACAAGGUGAACCUGAACACCAUCAAGCGCUGCCUCCUCAUCGACUACAACCCCGACUCCCAGGAGCUGGACUUCCGCCACUAUAGCAUCAAAGUUGUUCCUGUGGGCGCGAGUCGCGGGAUGAAGAAGCUGCUCCAGGAGAAGUUCCCCAACAUGAGCCGCCUGCAGGACAUCAGCGAGCUGCUGGCCACGGGCGCGGGGCUGUCGGAGAGCGAGGCAGAGCCUGACGGCGACCACAACAUCACAGAGCUGCCUCAGGCUGUCGCUGGCCGUGGCAACAUGCGGGCCCAGCAGAGUGCAGUGCGGCUCACCGAGAUCGGCCCGCGGAUGACACUGCAGCUCAUCAAGGUCCAGGAGGGCGUCGGGGAGGGCAAAGUGAUGUUCCACAGUUUUGUGAGCAAGACGGAGGAGGAGCUGCAGGCCAUCCUGGAAGCCAAGGAGAAGAAGCUGCGGCUGAAGGCGCAGAGGCAGGCCCAGCAGGCCCAGAAUGUGCAGCGCAAGCAGGAGCAGCGGGAGGCCCACAGAAAGAAGAGCCUGGAGGGCAUGAAGAAGGCACGGGUCGGGGGUAGUGAUGAAGAGGCCUCUGGGAUCCCUUCAAGGACGGCGAGCCUGGAGUUGGGUGAGGACGAUGAUGAACAGGAAGAUGAUGACAUCGAGUAUUUCUGCCAGGCGGUGGGCGAGGCGCCCAGUGAGGACCUGUUCCCCGAGGCCAAGCAGAAACGGCUUGCCAAGUCUCCAGGGCGGAAGCGGAAGCGGUGGGAAAUGGAUCGAGGCAGGGGUCGCCUUUGUGACCAGAAGUUUCCCAAGACCAAGGACAAGUCCCAGGGAGCCCAGGUGCCAAGUCCUGCCCUGCCAACUUCUUGGCAGCUGCCGACGACAAACUCAGUGGGUUCCAGGGGGACUUCCUGUGGCCCAUACUGGUGGUUGAGUUCCUGGUGGCCGUGGCCAGCAAUGGCCUGGCCCUGUACCGCUUCAGCAUCCGGAAGCAGCGCCCAUGGCACCCCGCCGUGGUCUUCUCUGUCCAGCUGGCAGUCAGCGACCUGCUCUGCGCCCUGACGCUGCCCCCGCUGGCCGCCUACCUCUAUCCCCCCAAGCACUGGCGCUAUGGGGAGGCCGCGUGCCGCCUGGAGCGCUUCCUCUUCACCUGCAACCUGCUGGGCAGCGUCAUCUUCAUCACCUGCAUCAGCCUCAACCGCUACCUGGGCAUCGUGCACCCCUUCUUCGCCCGAAGCCACCUGCGACCCAAGCACGCCUGGGCCGUGAGCGCUGCCGGCUGGGUCCUGGCCGCCCUGCUGGCCAUGCCCACACUCAGCUUCUCCCACCUGAAGAGGCCGCAGCAGGGGGCGGGCAACUGCAGCGUGGCCAGGCCCGAGGCCUGCAUCAAGUGUCUGGGGACAGCAGACCACGGGCUGGCGGCCUACAGAGCGUAUAGCCUGGUGCUGGCGGGGUUGGGCUGCGGCCUGCCGCUGCUGCUCACGCUGGCAGCCUACGGCGCCCUCGGGCGGGCCGUGCUACGCAGCCCAGGCAUGACUGUGGCCGAGAAGCUGCGUGUGGCAGCGUUGGUGGCCAGUGGUGUGGCCCUCUACGCCAGCUCCUAUGUGCCCUACCACAUCAUGCGGGUGCUCAACGUGGAUGCUCGGCGGCGCUGGAGCACCCGCUGCCCGAGCUUUGCAGACAUAGCCCAGGCCACAGCAGCCCUGGAGCUGGGGCCCUACGUGGGCUACCAGGUGAUGCGGGGCCUCAUGCCCCUGGCCUUCUGUGUCCACCCUCUACUCUACAUGGCCGCAGUGCCCAGCCUGGGCUGCUGCUGCCGACACUGCCCCGGCUACAGGGACAGCUGGAACCCAGAGGACGCCAAGAGCACUGGCCAAGCCCUGCCCCUCAAUGCCACAGCCGCCCCUAAACCGUCAGAGCCCCAGUCCCGUGAGCUGAGCCAAUGAUGUGGCCUAGCGGAAGCUGCCUCCUCACCCUAGGUGUUGCUGGAGAACCCUGAGGGCAGGGCCCGAGCCCCGACACAUCCCUUCCCCCAAAAAGCAACACCUGUGCUUGCAGCCAGGUCAGGCCCAGCUGCAGCCCAGGCAGGAGCAGUCGCCUUUCCCACCCACAGCGCUGGCCACAGGGCUCCCUGCAGGGUCAGGGACCAGACCACGCCCAGAGGAGGGGAGGCACUGGCCCCCGCCACAGGACUGGAGACGCAAGAACAAAAAGAACCAAGUAGAGAGAGUGGAGCUGCUUUAUUGCCCUUGGAGCCCGCGCUCUCGGAGGCUGUCUUCUGUCGCCAAGGGUCCCGGACCGAGUACACAGUGGCAGCUGGCUUAGUUGGUGGACGGCCUGGGGUAGGGGAGGGUGGCAGGUAUAAGACUUCUGGGGGCACCCCAAGACCCCAGACACCCAAGUGGCAUCUUGGGGGUGGGUGGGCAGAGGACGGGGUAAUGUGAGGACGAAGCGGGCACGGAGCCAGAUGGCCAGUCUCCAGGCCUGGUCCACGGACUGGCAGGGACCCCAGGCACAAGAGCUGCCACCCCUCUGCCCGGUUUUGGAAAAAAACAAUAAAGGACUGUCCCCUCAAAACCA